GUAUUUCCUGUGGUGGGUUCACACGCAGCUAGACACAGCUAACUUGAGUCUUGGAGCUCCUAGAGGGAAGCUUCUGGAAAGGAAGGCUCUUCAGGACCUCUUAGGAGCCAGUGCCUAGGAAAGUUGUCCCCUUGAAUGUCAGUGUGAAGGUGAAGGAGGAAGCAGAUGCCUGUUCAUAUGGAAACAAAGACCUGGCUGUGAAGAGGGGAGGCGGACACCAAAGUCCUGACACUUGGGCGGGACAGAAUUGAUCUGUGAGAGACUCAUCUAGUUCAUACCCUAGGUGACCCUGGGGGUGGCAUGGGGGUAGAUUAGAGAUCCCAGUCUGGUAUCCUCUGGAGAGUAGGAGUCCCAGGAGCUGAAGGUUUCUGGCCACUGAACUUUGGCUAAAGCAGAGGUGUCACAGCUGCUCAAGAUUCCCUGGUUAAAAAGUGAAAGUGAAAUAGAGGGUCGGGGCAGUGCUUUCCCAGAAGGAUUGCUCGGCAUCCUGCCCUUCCCAGAAGCAGCUCUGGUGCUGAAGAGAGCACUGCCUCCCUGUGUGACUGGAGAAGAGGACGUUGUCACAGAUAAAGAGCCAGGCUCACCAGCUCCUGACGCAUGCAUCAUGACCAUGAGACACAACUGGACACCAGACCUCAGCCCUUUGUGGGUCCUGCUCCUGUGUGCCCACGUCGUCACUCUCCUGGUCAGAGCCACACCUGUCUCGCAGACCACCACAGCUGCCACUGCCUCAGUUAGAAGCACAAAGGACCCCUGCCCCUCCCAGCCCCCAGUGUUCCCAGCAGCUAAGCAGUGUCCAGCAUUGGAAGUGACCUGGCCAGAGGUGGAAGUGCCACUGAAUGGAACGCUGAGCUUAUCCUGUGUGGCCUGCAGCCGCUUCCCCAACUUCAGCAUCCUCUACUGGCUGGGCAAUGGUUCCUUCAUUGAGCACCUCCCAGGCCGACUGUGGGAGGGGAGCACCAGCCGGGAACGUGGGAGCACAGGUACGCAGCUGUGCAAGGCCUUGGUGCUGGAGCAGCUGACCCCUGCCCUGCACAGCACCAACUUCUCCUGUGUGCUCGUGGACCCUGAACAGGUUGUCCAGCGUCACGUCGUCCUGGCCCAGCUCUGGGCUGGGCUGAGGGCAACCUUGCCCCCCACCCAAGAAGCCCUGCCCUCCAGCCACAGCAGUCCACAGCAGCAGGGUUAAGACUCAGCACAGGGCCAGCAGCAGCACAACCUUGACCAGAGCUUGGGUCCUACCUGUCUACCUGGAGUGAACAGUCCCUGACUGCCUGUAGGCUGCGUGGAUGCGCAACACACCCCCUCCUUCUCUGCUUUGGGUCCCUUCUCUCACCAAAUUCAAACUCCAUUCCCACCUACCUAGAAAAUCACAGCCUCCUUAUAAUGCCUCCUCCUCCUGCCAUUCUCUCUCCACCUAUCCAUUAGCCUUCCUAACGUCCUACUCCUCACACUGCUCUACUGCUCAGAAACCACCAAGACUGUUGAUGCCUUAGCCUUGCACUCCAGGGCCCUACCUGCAUUUCCCACAUGACUUUCUGGAAGCCUCCCAACUAUUCUUGCUUUUCCCAGACAGCUCCCACUCCCAUGUCUCUGCUCAUUUAGUCCCGUCUUCCUCACCGCCCCAGCAGGGGAACGCUCAAGCCUGGUUGAAAUGCUGCCUCUUCAGUGAAGUCAUCCUCUUUCAGCUCUGGCCGCAUUCUGCAGACUUCCUAUCUUCGUGCUGUAUGUUUUUUUUUUCCCCCUUCACUCUAAUGGACUGUUCCAGGGAAGGGAUGGGGGCAGCAGCUGCUUCGGAUCCACACUGUAUCUGUGUCAUCCCCACAUGGGUCCUCAUAAAGGAUUAUUCAAUGGAGGCAUCCUGACAUCUGUUCAUUUAGGCUUCAGUUCCACUCCCAGGAACUUUGCCUGUCCCACGAGGGAGUAUGGGAGAGAGGGACUGCCACACAGAAGCUGAAGACAACACCUGCUUCAGGGGAACACAGGCGCUUGAAAAAGAAAAGAGAGAACAGCCCAUAAUGCUCCCCGGGAGCAGAGGCCACUAAUGGAGAGUGGGAAGAGCCUGGAAAGAUGUGGCCUCAGGAAAAGGGAUGAGAGAAAGGAGGUGGUAUGGAAGACUCAGCAGGAACAAGGGGCUUGCUCACCACCUUCUCCCUGGAGAGGGCAGAAGAGGUCACACGCAGAGACUGCUACUACAUCUUACUCACCUGCCAAGGCUUGGUGGCCAACACCCAGAGGAACAAAUUAAGGACCGGGAAUUAAUUCCCAGGGGCUCCCUGGUGCCCAAAGGACAAGAGCUUCCAAGAAGAGUCUGGCCAGCCUGGCCUUUCCAGCAGCCCAUCACCGCCUGAGAAGGGCAUGGAGGACUCCCCACAGCUAAGUGUCACAAUUGUGCUGGGAAUCCCGGGCCCUUAACUCUGGCUAAGAGUGCCCCCAACACAGCCAGCCCCUAGAUGGGCAGGUAAGGAAGGCCCUGAGGCUGCAGGAAGGAGGGGCAGGUGGAGCUGGAUGGUAGCAAGGAGGCCAGCCUUGGAUUUUUAAAAAGCUUUCCUCUUUUCCCUGUGCCACGAUCCACCUUCCAGUCUAAUUUUGGGGUAUAGUAAGUCCCUGUAGUCCCCUCACCUGGAGGGGCCCCACUGGACACCCCGGCCUGGGAACGACGAGCAGAACUGCGAGUGGUGGGGCGGUAGCCAGGCAAGCUGAGCAGGGCUGAGUUGCCAUAAUCGGGAGAACCCAGGCGAGCUAGAGACUGAGUAGAGGAGGUGGCUCGCAGGCUAGCCUGGGAAGCAGGAGCAGACCGCGUGCUGUAGAACGAUGAGUUGGCGCUGUCUGGCUCUUCCACAUCUAGCUUCUGGAAGACAGAGUGAAUCUGUUGCAGUGUACAGUCCCUGGCACUGUACAGAAGCUUCCCAUUCCCUUCCGAAGCCCUCAGAUCCCACGGCACAUCCAUGUAUUCCCAACUGCUUUGCAAAGGUCCUUAAAGUGUGUGUCUGCAAGAAAUGGGCCUUGUCGACAGAAGCCCUCACAAGGUGGUGCUGAUGUUGUCAAGACUCUUCUACGCAUUUUUUUCAUGGAGUCUAUUCAUAAUGCUUUGAGGUAGGGAAUGCAGAGUGUUUAUCGGCCCAUUUUGGAGAUGAAGUGCAAAGAAAUAAAGUGACUAGCCCCAAAUCACACUGCUAGGAAGUAUCAGAGCUGGGGCUAGGCCCCAUGUCUCCUGACUAGUCAGGCUCAUCCCACAGCCUCUGCUGUCCCUCAGUCCAAACUUCCAGGGCCCUUACCAUGUUCCAGAACUUCCCCAACUUCUUGGUAGCAGGGGGCACCCUAAACACACAGGUCCCCCCUGCUGUACCAGGGGCCCCUCUCCCCUCCUCCCAAACCUCCCCUUCAAGAUGUGGAAACAAAGGCAAGGGCCUGUAGCCUGUCAGGCAGUCCACUGGGCAGCAACAAUGCCUCUCAGCUGCAUGGGGCAUGCUGGGAGGCACAGGAUGGGCUGCAGCUUCGCCACGUUCUCUCCCUUCACCCUGCACAGGCUCAGUGCUACGCAUGGAGAGAAUGCUAGCCUUAGUCAGGAGGCAGGGAUCUAAUCCUAGCCCUGCCUUUUUCUUCAGAAGUGCCCUUAACCAAGUCACUGCCCUUUUUAAGACCUCUCAGCUUUCCCACUGUAACAUGGACUGGCUGCUCAUCCCUCCCUGCUCCUGACUGAGUGCCCAGUGCAAAGAUGCCCUUGAGAGGAAGUGGGAAUUGCUGCCCUGCAGCCCCUGUCCCAGCAGCCUGACCUUGGUCAUGGUGAUGUUGAUGAUCUGCGUGGUGCGCCGACGAGCGGAGCGGGUCUUACGACCCGAGUCCAGGAAGACGUCUCCCAGGGAGUCCAGGCUGCUCUCCAGGGGGGCCUGACUCCGAGCAGGGAUGGGAGUGAAGUAGAGACUCUCCAGGGAUUCUACCUUGGGGGGCAGGCGCUGGGAGAUAGGUGAGGCUGGUUCUCCAGGGACGCUGGUGCCGUCUGGCUGGGUACGAGGCAGCUUGCUAUGGAAAGGAAACCUGCUGAGGUACAGUCCUUCACGCUAGAAGGCAUUUUGUCCAGCCCUUUUUGAAAGUGACCAUUUCCCAUCCUUACUACAAGCAGAUGAGGUCAAGCAGCCCAUCUCUCUGAUUUUUCAGAGGUACCAAGGAAAGCACUUGACCUGGGCCUUCCUUUCAGUCCACUCCCCUGGCUUCUCCUAAUAGCUCCUCAUAGUGGCAAUGCCCAGACCCAGAUGUCCCAUCCCCACCAGAUGCCCAUGGCUGCUUCACAGCAAACACGUCCCAAUCUAAGCCCACUUCUCUGUUCUUCCUCCUGCAUCUCCCAUUUCAGUGAAUAGGAACGCCCCCCACUCAGGCCCCCAAGCCAUGAACGUGGGCAUAAUCCAAUGUCGUCCUGCUUGGCGAGCCCAAUCACCAAGCUUCCUGAACAGCUCCUAACCACACCCCACUCCAUGCUCAUGUCCUUUCCCUGGUCUGCUUCAUCUCCUCUCACCUAGACUCAUCAUGGCACUGACAGAGGAAGAUGAGUGGUGACAAGCCAAGAACUCAGGCCAGGCUGCCCAGGGUCAAACCCCAGCUCUACCACUGGGGAACCUUGGGCAAGUGACUGCCCCUCUAUGCCCCAGAUUCAUCUGUUAAAGGAGACAGAAUAAACCUACCUCAGAGGGUUGUUGGGGGACAAAUCAGGUAUAAUUGUCAUGAGUGCUUUAUGUCUAGCACAAAAUAAGUAAAUGUAAGUGUUUAAUAAAAACAUUUUUCCAGUCUUAA